AGAGGACUCACUCUCUGCCAACGGUAUCGCUUCACCUUCGUGCUUUGCCUGAGAUCUCCCAAAUCCAAGUGGAAUUUGGUGUGCACAGCCAUACUGUGUAUUUGUAUCUUCUCUCCCCCUCUCCUUCUUUCCCCCCACCUUCGCCGUCUGACCAAUGCUGGGAUCUGAGAUCUAGUCGCCCCCUUCCUGCCUCCUUUCCGCCUCUCCCCACCCUUUUCUUCUCUCAUCUACACGCCACCAACCCCCACUCCCACCCACCUAAAGGGCAAAGAGCAAAGACACCCUGGAAAAGCAAGGGCUAAUUCCAUCUUCUCGGAUGGAAGGAGGCCUCGGGCAGGGAUUGCGCUGUGAGUGACAACCUUUGAGGAAGAGAGAAAGAGAGAAAUCCAGAGACUGAGCUCAGGCUCUCGGGAACAACGAAGCUCUCCACUGAUCCAGAGCACCGAGAUUUUAAAUCAAAGGAACCUAGUCCUGGGACACUCACUCUGCCUGCCUGCCUACCAACCAUCGAGGGCAUAGGGAGCUGUGGUCGUGAGCUCCCUGUCGCUGGCAUCGCCGCGCUAGGUGCGCGCCCCGCUCUCCCAUUGGUAUGCAGCGACCAUUUCCCUGCAAGUCUCAAAGGUGGAAACAUUUAAACGGAUUACAAGCGUGAUUCGGUAGCCUUUCGGAAAGUUGGUGGCCAGAAGAGGAGAAGCUACAAGGCUACAGUAUGAUGGAUACAAUUCAGCUUCGCAGAGAGUUUGCCCCUCCUGCUGGGUAGCCCCUCGCAGCAAACCUCGGAGAUCCUGAGCGCUCUGCACCAUAGUUUUGUAAUCAACCACGAACGAUGAAACCUUCCAUAGCUGAGAUGCUUCACAGAGGAAGGAUGUUGUGGAUAAUUCUUCUAAGCACAAUUGCUCUAGGAUGGACUACCCCGAUUCCCCUAAUAGAGGACUCAGAGGAAAUAGAUGAGCCCUGUUUUGAUCCAUGCUACUGUGAAGUUAAAGAAAGCCUCUUUCAUAUACAUUGUGACAGUAAAGGAUUUACAAAUAUUAGUCAGAUUACCGAGUUCUGGUCAAGACCUUUUAAACUGUAUCUGCAGAGGAAUUCUAUGAGGAAAUUAUAUACCAACAGUUUUCUUCAUUUGAAUAAUGCUGUGUCUAUUAAUCUUGGGAACAAUGCAUUGCAGGACAUUCAGACUGGAGCUUUCAAUGGUCUUAAGAUUUUAAAGAGACUAUAUCUACAUGAAAACAAACUAGAUGUCUUCAGAAAUGACACCUUCCUUGGCUUGGAAAGUCUAGAAUAUCUGCAGGCAGAUUACAAUGUCAUUAAACGUAUUGAGAGUGGGGCAUUUCGGAACCUAAGUAAAUUGAGGGUUCUGAUUUUAAAUGAUAAUCUCAUCCCCAUGCUUCCAACCAAUUUAUUUAAGGCUGUCUCUUUAACCCAUUUGGACCUACGUGGAAAUAGGUUAAAGGUUCUUUUUUACCGAGGAAUGCUAGAUCACAUUGGCAGAAGCCUGAUGGAGCUCCAGCUGGAAGAAAACCCUUGGAACUGUACAUGUGAAAUUGUACAACUGAAGAGUUGGCUGGAACGCAUUCCUUAUACUGCCCUGGUGGGAGACAUUACCUGUGAGACCCCUUUCCACUUCCAUGGAAAGGACCUACGAGAAAUCAGGAAGACAGAACUCUGUCCCUUGUUGUCUGACUCUGAGGUAGAGGCUAGUUUGGGAAUUCCACAUUCGUCAUCAAGUAAGGAGAAUGCAUGGCCAACUAAGCCUUCCUCAAUGCUAUCCUCUGUUCAUUUUACUGCUUCUUCUGUCGAAUACAAGUCCUCAAAUAAACAGCCUAAGCCCACCAAACAGCCUCGAACACCAAGGCCACCCUCCACCUCCCAAGCUUUAUAUCCUGGUCCAAACCAGCCUCCCAUUGCUCCUUAUCAGACCAGACCACCAAUCCCCAUUAUAUGCCCCACUGGGUGUACCUGUAAUUUGCACAUCAAUGACCUUGGCUUGACUGUCAACUGCAAAGAGCGAGGAUUUAAUAACAUUUCUGAACUUCUUCCAAGGCCCUUGAAUGCCAAGAAACUGUAUCUGAGUAGCAAUCUGAUUCAGAAAAUAUACCGUUCUGAUUUUUGGAAUUUUUCUUCCUUGGAUCUCUUGCAUCUGGGGAACAAUCGUAUUUCCUAUGUCCAAGAUGGGGCCUUUAUCAACUUGCCCAACUUAAAGAGCCUCUUCCUUAAUGGCAACGAUAUAGAGAAGCUGACACCAGGCAUGUUCCGAGGCCUACAGAGUUUGCACUACUUGUACUUUGAGUUCAAUGUCAUCCGGGAAAUCCAGCCUGCAGCCUUCAGCCUCAUGCCCAACUUGAAGCUGCUAUUCCUCAAUAAUAACUUACUGAGGACUCUGCCAACAGACGCCUUUGCUGGCACAUCCCUGGCCCGGCUCAACCUGAGGAAGAACUACUUCCUCUAUCUUCCCGUGGCUGGUGUCCUGGAACACUUGAAUGCCAUUGUCCAGAUAGACCUCAAUGAGAAUCCUUGGGACUGCACCUGUGACCUGGUCCCCUUUAAACAGUGGAUCGAAACCAUCAGCUCAGUCAGUGUGGUUGGUGAUGUGCUUUGCAGGAGCCCUGAGAACCUCACGCACCGUGAUGUGCGCACUAUUGAGCUGGAAGUUCUUUGCCCAGAGAUGCUGCACGUUGCACCAGCUGGAGAAUCCCCAGCCCAGCCUGGAGAUUCUCACCUUAUUGGGGCACCAACCAGUGCAUCACCUUAUGAGUUUUCUCCUCCUGGGGGCCCUGUGCCACUUUCUGUGUUAAUUCUCAGCCUGCUGGUUCUGUUUUUCUCAGCAGUCUUUGUUGCUGCAGGCCUCUUUGCCUACGUGCUCCGAAGGCGUCGAAAGAAGCUGCCCUUCAGAAGCAAGCGGCAGGAAGGUGUGGACCUUACUGGCAUCCAAAUGCAAUGCCACAGGCUGUUUGAGGAUGGUGGAGGUGGUGGUGGCGGAAGUGGGGGUGGUGGUCGACCAACUCUUUCCUCUCCAGAGAAGGCCCCUCCCGUGGGUCAUGUGUAUGAGUACAUCCCCCACCCGGUUACCCAAAUGUGCAACAACCCCAUCUACAAGCCUCGUGAGGAGGAGGAGGUGGCUGUUUCAUCAGCCCAAGAAGCAGGGAGUGCAGAACGUGGGGGUCCAGGGACACAACCACCGGGAAUGGGUGAGGCUCUCCUAGGAAGUGAGCAGUUUGCUGAGACACCCAAGGAGAACCAUAGUAACUACCGGACCUUGCUGGAAAAAGAGAAGGAGUGGGCCCUAGCAGUGUCCAGCUCCCAGCUUAACACCAUAGUGACGGUGAAUCACCAUCACCCUCACCACCCAGCAGUUGGUGGGGUUUCAGGAGUAGUUGGGGGAACUGGGGGAGACUUGGCAGGGUUCCGCCACCAUGAGAAAAAUGGUGGGGUGGUGCUGUUUCCUCCUGGGGGAGGCUGUGGUAGUGGCAGUAUGCUACUAGAUCGAGAGAGGCCACAGCCUGCCCCCUGCACAGUGGGAUUUGUGGACUGUCUCUAUGGAACAGUGCCCAAAUUAAAGGAACUGCACGUGCACCCUCCUGGCAUGCAAUACCCAGACUUACAGCAGGAUGCCAGGCUCAAAGAAACCCUUCUCUUCUCGGCUGGAAAGGGCUUCACAGACCACCAAACCCAAAAAAGUGAUUACCUCGAGUUAAGGGCCAAACUUCAAACCAAGCCGGAUUACCUCGAAGUCCUGGAGAAGACAACAUACAGGUUCUAACAGAGAGAAGAAAAUAUAUUAGUGCUUUUUUUUUUUCAAAAGAAAAGGAAAAUAAAAGAAAUAUAUCCCUUGCUCCCUUUACACUUGUCCCAGUAACUCCAUCCUCACGAUCUUUCCUACCCUGAACAAAACUAAAACCGCAUGAUAACUAGAGAAUACAGAUGUAUGCUCUCCCCUCUCAGAUGCGAUUUGGAGGAAGGGCCAUACUCAGAUCAUUAAUCAAUGAAAGUGCCUUCGCAGACUUUUGCCAGCAAAUGUUAUCAUUAUUUUUUUAUACUGAAACUUGAGACUUUGACUGUGCCAUGUAUAAGAUAUACUGGGGAUCAUUGUAUGGAUCCUAAUUAAGUAAAAUUCAAUGUGUCUUUUUAUUUUCAGUAACUAUUUUUUUUAUAGUUGUAGUUUUGAUUUAAAGGGGGGGAAACAAGUUGACAUUUGUCAUUUGUGGCUUUCUUUCUUAUCAUCAUGGCACAGAUUCUGUACAUGUAUUAACAAUGCAGUUUGCUGCAUGCCUGGAAACUGCAAGAUGGGGAGGGAGGGGGCGGGUCUUGCUCGAAUGUUCUCACUCACUAUCUUGUCUCUCAUACACAUAUCCAUCUGCAGACCAUGGUCCCUAAACCUGCAGUUUCUUCCUGCUGGUGCAGGUACACACACACACACACACACACACACACACACACACACACACUCCAUACCAUUUCCAUUCAACUCAAUCUGCUUAGUUCGGGUUUGAUCCAUUUUUCUCCUCUCCAUAGUUCUACCACCCUUCACUGCUAGUGUACAGCUCACAGCAUCUCUCCUACCACCCUGGGAAAAGUCACAUUCUAGGCUGGAUUCUACUGAAGUAGAGGCCUGGUGGUUUAACAGCCGAAGACACACGCCUAGGGAUGAGCACCCUCUUUGUGACACUUCAUCCUGAUGCCAAGAUUUUUUGGAGAACAUCUGCACUUUCUUAUAUAUAUAUAUAAUAUUAAAAAAAGCAACUGGGUAUAUAUCACUAACAGCUUUGUAGGAAGCACUUUUAAUGUUUUCUCUCUCACACACAAAGAUUCAAAAGAAAUGUGCAUAUAUUUAUUCUGUAAUUUCAGUGAUUAUAAAUUGUAAAGGUAAUGUUUAAUCAUUGUAUAGUGAUUAUGCCUCUGGUAUAGCUUUCCUAAUAAAAAGUUUUUGAAAAACAUAA